GUCGAGGCGCCAAGGCGCUCGUUUGGCGCGCGCGCCCUAGGCGGCGGAUCUAAGCUAACUUCUUGGAUCUUUUCUUGUUUCUCCUUGGUUUUUGACUUUUUCUGGACCCUGGUGUCUACGAUUUCCGAGAUGCCGUCUUCUUUGUUGGGCGCGGCGAUGCCGGCCUCUACAUCUGCCGCAGCCCUGCAGGAAGCUCUGGAAAAUGCUGGACGGCUCAUCGACCGUCAGUUGCAAGAGGACCGCAUGUACCCGGACCUUUCCGAGCUGCUUAUGGUGUCUGCCCCAAGUGAGUGAUAGUGACCCUGCUUUCUCAACCUAAAGGACUCUCGCCUGACUUCCUAAUUUGCUACUUAUCCCCAGCGUUGGUCCCGGCGAGGAUAUGCUGAGAUUUAUGGCACUGUUGGCUGCAUUUUUGGAGAACAGCAAGCAGCUUCUUUUCAGAUAAUCCCACCGUUUCUGGCAUGUCAGAUAUGGAUUAUCCUUUGCAAGGACCUGGUUUGCUGUCCGUACCCAACCUUCCAGAGAUCAGUUCCAUCCGAAGAGUUCCUCUCCCACCUGAACUUGUUGAGCAGUUUGGACAUAUGCAGUGUAAUUGCAUGAUGGGUGUGUUCCCUCCUAUCAGCAGAGCUUGGCUCACAAUUGACAGUGAUAUAUUCAUGUGGAACUAUGAGGAUGGAGGAGACCUUGCCUAUUUUGAUGGACUUAGUGAGACUAUUCUUGCUGUGGGGCUUGUGAAGCCAAAAGCAGGCAUCUUUCAACCUCAUGUGCGACACCUCCUGGUUUUGGCGACCCCUGUAGACAUAGUAAUUCUUGGACUCAGCUAUGCUAAUUUGCAAACAGGUUCUGGAGUUCUUAAUGAUAGUUUGUCUGGUGGAAUGCAGUUGCUUCCAGAUCCUUUAUAUUCUCUUCCUACUGAUAAUACUUACCUUUUAACAAUAACUUCCACUGAUAAUGGCAGAAUUUUCUUGGCUGGAAAGGAUGGCUGUUUAUAUGAAGUAGCCUACCAGGCUGAAGCAGGGUGGUUUAGCCAAAGAUGUAGGAAAAUAAACCACUCAAAGAGCUCACUUUCUUUCCUUGUUCCUUCCUUGCUACAAUUCACGUUCUCAGAAGAUGAUCCUAUUCUUCAAAUUGCAAUUGAUAAUUCUAGAAAUAUUUUAUAUACACGAUCUGAGAAAGGAGUAAUACAGGUGUAUGAUUUGGGACAAGAUGGACAAGGAAUGAGCAGAGUUGCCUCUGUGUCACAGAAUGCCAUUGUCUCUGCUGCUGGUAACAUUGCUAGGACCAUCGAUCGUUCUGUUUUUAAACCAAUUGUCCAAAUAGCAGUGAUUGAAAAUUCUGAAUCACUGGACUGUCAGUUAUUGGCUGUCACACAUGCAGGUGUUAGGUUAUAUUUUAGCACUUGUCCAUUCAGACAGCCAUUAGCACGGCCUAAUACACUGACGCUGGUUCAUGUCCGCUUACCUCCUGGAUUCUCAGCAUCUUCAACCGUGGAAAAGCCUUCAAAAGUACAUAGAGCUCUUUAUAGUAAAGGUAUUCUAUUGAUGGCAGCCUCAGAAAAUGAGGAUAAUGAUAUUUUAUGGUGUGUCAACCAUGAUACUUUUCCUUUCCAAAAGCCAAUGAUGGAAACCCAGAUGACAGCUGGUGUUGAUGGUCAUUCCUGGGCUCUUUCUGCGAUAGAUGAAUUGAAAGUAGAUAAAAUAAUUACACCUUUAAACAAGGAUCAUAUUCCAAUAACUGAUUCACCAGUUGUUGUACAGCAGCACAUGUUACCUCCGAAGAAAUUUGUUCUCCUCUCAGCACAGGGGAGCCUUAUGUUUCAUAAACUUAGACCUGUAGAUCAACUGAGGCAUCUACUUGUGAGUAAUGUGGGAGGAGAUGGAGAAGAGAUUGAAAGAUUCUUUAAAUUACAUCAGGAAGACCAGGCUUGUGCAACUUGCCUUAUUCUUGCUUGCUCCACUGCUGCCUGUGAUAGAGAAGUAUCUGCCUGGGCUACUCGGGCUUUCUUUAGGUAUGGUGGUGAAGCACAGAUGAGAUUUCCAACCACUCUUCCGCCUCCAAGUAAUGUUGGUCCCAUCUUGGGGUCUCCUGUCUAUUCUAGUUCUCCUGUUCCUAGUGGUAGUCCCUAUCCAAAUCCAUCCUUUUUGGGAACACCGUCUCAUGGUAUACAGCCUCCUGCCAUGUCAACUCCAGUGUGUGCUCUGGGAAACCCAGCAACUCAGGCCACAAAUAUGAGUUGUGUGACUGGACCAGAGAUUGUGUACUCUGGAAAACACAAUGGUAUUUGCAUUUACUUUUCUCGGAUCAUGGGAAACAUUUGGGAUGCAAGCUUAGUUGUGGAGAGAAUAUUCAAGAGUGGCAACAGAGAGAUCACUGCAAUUGAAAGUAGUGUUCCCUGCCAACUGCUAGAGUCAGUGCUACAAGAACUAAAGGGUUUGCAGGAAUUUCUAGACAGAAACUCCCAGUUUGCAGGAGGACCAUUAGGAAAUCCAAAUACUACUGCUAAAGUGCAGCAGAGGCUGAUAGGAUUCAUGCGUCCUGAAAACGGAAAUCCCCAGCAAAUGCAACAGGAACUGCAGAGGAAGUUUCAUGAGGCUCAACUAAGUGAAAAGAUUUCACUUCAGGCAAUUCAGCAGUUGGUUCGAAAAUCAUAUCAGGCUCUGGCUUUAUGGAAACUUCUUUGUGAACAUCAAUUCACUAUCAUUGUGGCAGAACUUCAGAAGGAACUUCAAGAGCAGCUGAAGAUCACCACCUUUAAAGAUCUUGUAAUCAGGGACAAAGAACUCACAGGGGCAUUAAUUGCUUCUCUUAUCAACUGCUACAUCAGAGAUAAUGCCGCUGUUGAUGGCAUUAGUUUACAUUUACAGGAUAUCUGCCCACUUCUAUAUAGCACUGAUGAUGCAAUUUGUUCUAAGGCAAAUGAGCUUCUCCAGCGUUCCCGACAAGUUCAAAAUAAGACUGAAAAAGAAAGAAUGUUAAGGGAAUCAUUAAAGGAAUAUCAAAAAAUUAGCAAUCAAGUGGACCUUUCCAAUGUUUGUGCUCAGUAUAGACAAGUGAGAUUUUAUGAGGGUGUGGUGGAACUUUCUCUUACGGCUGCAGAGAAAAAAGAUCCUCAAGGUCUUGGGCUUCAUUUCUAUAAACAUGGAGAACCAGAAGAAGACAUAGUUGGACUUCAGGCCUUCCAAGAAAGAUUAAACAGUUACAAAUGCAUUACAGACACACUUCAAGAACUGGUAAAUCAAAGUAAGGCCGCUCCUCAGUCUCCCAGUGUACCCAAAAAACCUGGUCCUCCAGUGUUGUCAUCUGAUCCAAAUAUGCUGAGUAAUGAAGAAGCAGGACAUCAUUUUGAACAAAUGCUUAAAUUGUCACAGCGAUCCAAGGAUGAGCUCUUUAGUAUUGCCCUUUAUAAUUGGCUAAUACAAGUCGACCUUGCAGAUAAGCUGCUACAGGUUGCUUCUCCAUUUCUGGAGCCACAUCUAGUCCGAAUGGCCAAAGUUGAUCAAAACAGAGUUCGUUAUAUGGAUUUACUCUGGCGGUAUUACGAGAAGAACAGAAGUUUCAGUAAUGCUGCUCGUGUACUGUCCAGACUGGCUGACAUGCAUAGCACAGAAAUUUCACUUCAGCAGCGACUAGAGUACAUUGCUCGAGCCAUUCUUAGUGCCAAAAGUUCCACUGCCAUUUCAUCAAUAGCUGCCGAUGGUGAAUUUCUUCAUGAAUUAGAAGAAAAAAUGGAGGUUGCUAGGAUCCAACUUCAGAUACAGGAGACACUACAAAGGCAGUAUUCCCAUCAUUCUUCUGUACAGGAUGCAGUUUCUCAGCUGGAUUCUGAGCUGAUGGACAUAACUAAGCUUUAUGGGGAAUUUGCUGACCCAUUUAAACUUGCAGAGUGCAAACUUGCAAUAAUUCAUUGUGCCGGUUAUUCAGACCCUAUAUUGGUGCAGACACUUUGGCAAGAUAUCAUAGAGAAAGAAUUGAGUGACAGUGUGACAUUGAGCUCCUCGGAUAGAAUGCAUGCUCUUAGUCUCAAGAUUGUUCUCCUUGGCAAAAUUUAUGCUGGCACACCACGCUUCUUUCCUUUAGAUUUUAUUGUACAGUUUUUAGAACAGCAGGUUUGUACUUUGAACUGGGAUGUGGGCUUCGUAAUACAGACAAUGAAUGAAAUUGGAGUACCAUUACCUAGACUACUAGAAGUUUAUGAUCAGUUGUUCAAAUCACGGGAUCCAUUCUGGAACAGAAUGAAGAAGCCACUGCACCUUUUGGAUUGUAUACAUGUAUUAUUGAUAAGAUAUGUUGAGAAUCCCAGCCAAGUUUUAAAUUGUGAAAGGAGAAGAUUUACAAAUCUCUGCCUGGAUGCUGUUUGUGGUUACCUUGUUGAGCUCCAGUCUAUGAGCUCGUCAGUAGCAGUACAAGCCAUCACUGGGAAUUUUAAAUCUCUUCAAGCUAAAUUAGAACGGCUUCAUUAAUUACUGUGAUAUACUUUCAUCCGUUUUAUGAUCUGUAAAAUAAAAACUCAGCUGGGUCCAGAUAUCAGGUGUUCUAAAUCUAAGAAUGUAAGAACAAUCUUAAUAGAAAUAUGUUUUUAAUAAGUGGCUAAUAUCUACAAAUAGUACCUUUGCUAAAUGAAUUCUUUUUUAUGACUAUUUUGUUUUUUAGUAAUUGGGUGAAAAAACAACUGAAAUGAGAUUAUUUAUUAUUUUAACAUAAGGAUUAAAAAAAUUUAGAAACUCUUAUUUUGAAUUGUACUGCAGGCAGAAAUUUCGAAUUUAUAUUAUUCAUUUUCAAGUUAGUCCAAGGAUAUUGGCAUUAAAACUCCACUAGGCGGCCAGGCACAGUGACUUACACCUGUAAUCCCAGCACUUUGGGAGGCCAAGGUGGGCGAAUCACGAGGCCAAGAGUUUGAGACCAACCUGGCCAACAUGGUGAAACCCCAUCUCUACUAAAAAUACAAAAAAAAAUAGCCAGGCGUGGUGGCGGGCGCCUGUAAUCCCAGCUACUCGGGAGGCUGAGGGAGGCGAAUCACUUGAACCCGGGAGGCAGAGGUUUCAGUGAGUCAAAAUCGCACCAUUGCACUCCAGCCCAGGCAACAGGGCGAGACUCUGUCUCAAAAAACAAAAAAACCUCAAAUAGGCUAAGCAGAUCCAUUCCCAUAAUAGUGGAUUCUAAAACCGUCCUUAAAUAGGCAAAUAACUGACUUUUUCAAAACUUUUUUUAGGUGUUGGGUUCACCCUUGAAAGAACUGUCCUCUAACAACUGGUUUUGUCAGUUAAAGCCCUUGAGAAUUGACAUAGCUAUAUACCUGGUUGAGCAGGUGAUAAAACUUGUAACUAAUGUUGUGUCCUGAAAACCUACACAGGGAGGUACUGUUUUCCCUUAGUGUCUACCUGGCUGCUUGGCCUUGUGACUACUGAUUCCAUUAGAGCAGUGGUUCUCAAAGUAUGUGCUCCAAACCAGAAGCAUCAGCAUCAGCAUCAGCAUCACCUAGGAAUUUGUUAGAAAUGCAAAUUCUCGAGCCCCAACCCAGACCUACUGAAUCAAAAACGUGGGGGAUGAGGCCCUGCUUUCUAUGUUUUAACAAGCUCUCCAGGAGAUUUUGGUGCAUGUCAAAUUUGAAAGCCACUGCAGUAAAGGAUACUGCUACCUUCCAUAGUUUAUGGACUGAGCUACCUAUCUGGCUCCUCCUCUGUGAAUAACCACACACACAAAUUUUGCCCAAGGCACACAAUAUAUAAAGCAAAACUGUUAGUAAUGUACUUUUUAAUUAUUCCUUAACAAAAUAGAAUAACCAAACCAAAUGCUUCAAAGUAAUAGCAACAAGAGAGAAGAAGAGUGGGAAUGACCAGAGCUAACAAAACACUCUAUUCCUUUCUCUCUUUUUUUUUUUUUUGGAGACAGAAUCUCACCCUGUAGCCCAGCCUGGAGUGCAGUGGUGCGAUCCCGGCUCACUGCAACCUCUGCCUCACAGGUUUGAAGCAAUUUGCCUGCCUCAGCCUCUCGAGUAGCUGGGAUUGCAGGUGUGCGCCACCAUACCCAGCUAAUUUUUGUAUUUUUAGUAGAGAUGGGUUUCACCAUGUUGGCCAGGCUGGUCUUGAACUCCUGACCUCAAGUGAUCUGCCCGCCUCCACCUCCCAAAGUGUUGAGAUUACAGACGUGAGCCAAUGUGCCUGGCCUAUUCCCUUCUCUCUUUAUGCUACCACAAAUAAUUACCUUCUGUUUAUUGUAAGUGAUGCAUGUCUAACAAUUUGUACAAUACAUUUUGAAUAUAUUUUUCCUUCCAUUAUUGUCUUUUCCCAAGACCAUAGGGUUGCCUUCUCUACAUUUGUUCUCUUAGAAUUCAGCUCCCUUUUCCCUAUAAUCUUCUAAUGUAGAAUAUUUAAUAGAAUGCCAGAACGUCACUCAGUGGGUACUACUACCUCUUAUUUUUCAACUUUUCAGUUUCUUAAGUUUAGCGUUUUUUGAAUAUGUAAAGUGAAUGUAUGCGAUACAUUAAUUCGUUUUAUAAAUUUAAAAUUCUGUCAUGUCUACUUAAAAGGAAGGCCUUGUCUGAAUGUUGUAAUUUAGGUGUGACUCCAGUUCUGCUAGAGAUAAGAACUUCAUUUUUGUUUUAAGCACAUUUACAUACUAGCAAUAUGUUGUUAUAUAUACUCAGCUCACAACAUUGAAAGUACAUGUUUUAAAAGGGCUGUAGGCUUCCAUGGUUAGAUGGUCUGUUAGAGUCAGAAAUCUGAACACUGUCCUUUUAUUCACACAGCAUGCUUUGAGAGGUUUUAGGAAUUCCAGCCCCACAACAGAUGCUUGCAAUACCUUUUGGGGGGUAAGAUUCCUAAGAGAGAAGAAAUUAGGUCCCCUCAUUUUUACCCUUGGAACAGUGUUUCUAAAACUUUCACAUUCAGAACAAUCAGCCGGAUAGCCUGUUAUGACAGAUUCUUGAGUUCCAUCUGUAGUGUCAUGCUGAUCCUGGCAGUCAGUGGAUCAGAGUUGGAGUAGCAUUUAUCCACUGUAUUAGUAUACUUUGUACUUGGUGUUUGUUCAACGCAUUACUUUUUUGAAUUUUUUUGUUUUUUGAAGACAAGGGCUUGCCCUGGAGUGCAGUGGCAUGAUCUUGGCUCACUGCAGCCUCGAGCUCCUGGGCUCAACUCAGUCUUCCCACCUCAUCCUCUUAAAUAGCUGGGACUACAGGCACGUGCUGCUACACCCUGCUAUUGUCUGUUUGUUUGUUUGAGACUGAGUUUUGCUCUUGUUGCCCAGGCUGGAGUGCAAUGGCACAAUCUUGGCUCACCACAGCCUUUUUUAUGAGACUGAGUUUUGCUCUUGUUGCCCAGGCUGGAGUGCAAUGGCACGAUCUUGGCUCACCACAACCUCCACUUCCUGGGUUCAAGCAAUUCUUCUGCCUCAGCCUCCCGAGUAGCUGAGAUUACAGGCAUGCGCCACCAUGCCUGGCUAAUUUUUUUUUUUUGUAUUUUUAGUAGAGAUGGGGUUUCACCGUGUUGGUCAGGCUGGUCUUGAACUCCUGACCUCAGGUGAUCCACCCCCCUUGGCCUCCCAAAGAGCUGGGAUUACAGGCAUGAGCCACUGCGCCUAGCCCCACCCCCCCUACUUUUUUUUUUUUUUUUUUUUUAAUUUUUUGUGUAGCCAAAAGAUCUCACUCUGUUGCCCAGACUGCUCUCAAAACUCCUGGCCUUAAGUGAUUCCCCUGCCUCAGUCUCCCAAAGUGCUGGGAUUAUAGGCAUGAGCCACCAUGCCUGUCCAUUAUUUCUUUAUAGUGACUAUUAUAUGUAGGCAAUGUAUAAUUGGUAGAACAUAGUCUAUGAAACAGUGCGUUAAUUGUGGGCAGUGAAGAAUCAUUGAAGUUGUGAAAUUUGUAUUUUAACUAGAUCAUUGUAGUAUGGCAAAACGGUUAGGAAAGAGAAAGCUAUCUUGACUAACUGUUUAUGCUAUGAGAUACUGACUGAUGUACAUGUACAUUUAGUGUUUCUUUAGGUAUACCUGACUUAUUCAUUGAACACCUAUCCACUGAUCUCAAAAGUAUUCCUCAGGGUAGUCUCCAUUCCUGUCAUUUUUCCUCCUAUUCAUGAGACGGAAAAAUUAUGACCAUGGUACAGAGUUGUAUCAAGGAAAUGAAGAACUAGAACAUUGAAUUGAAAGGUUUUGAAAGGGUUCACAAUUUCUUUUCAUUUUCUAUUAAUGUCUUCUUUUAAAUUCUCUUAAGAAUAAAACUUUUUUCUAAUA